GCCUUUAUCAUGUGCUGAUGCUACUCUGCUUCUUCGCUGGCCCGGCAGGCCGGUGCACACUUUGUAGGAGCGGGCUUUGUCAUAAUCUUCUUUGUAGCCCCAGCCCUAGCUCAGCAGCGGAGCCCCUCAAACCUCGGGAACUCCUCCCUGCAAAGGAGCCAGGACGCCCUCCCUCAGGCUGCCUUUAACCAGGGCAGGGUGACAAAGGACCUCCACAGAGUAGGCGGUCACUGCCUUAGCAGUGAGGCCUCAGGGCCCGGGCAGGCACAGCCAGCGGGACUCGAAGCAGGCUGGCGCCGAGGCUCGUGUAGCCGCCUCACAGCUGCAGGCGGACUGUAAGUGCGCGCGCGGUCGCCAUGGCAGCGCAGCCGCCGCGGCCAGUGGGUGAGAGGAGCAUGGGGAGCUCCCGGGAGGCCGCCCGUGCGCCGGCCAGGUCCCCGGCUUGGGCCUCCACUCAGGCCAGUACUCCGGGCGCGGCCCUGGCGGUCCAGCGCGAAUCUCCAGAAUCUGGUCUCCAGAAACAUUAUUCUAAUCUGUGUAUGGAAAAAUCCCAGAAAAUUAAUCCUUUUAUAUUGCAUAUACUCCAAGAAGUGGAUGAAGAAAUUAAAAAGGGGCUAGCAGCAGGAAUCACAUUAAACAUUGCUGGUAACAAUCGCUUAGUGCCAGUAGAAAGAGUUACAGGUGAAGAUUUUUGGAUUCUUUCCAAAAUUUUAAAGAAUUGUCUGUAUAUUAAUGGUUUGGAUGUUGGAUAUAACCUUCUAUGUGAUGUUGGUGCAUACUAUGCUGCGAAACUGCUUCAGAAACAACUUAAUCUCAUUUACUUAAACCUCAUGUUUAAUGAUAUUGGGCCCGAAGGUGGAGAAUUGAUUGCUAAAGUGCUACAUAAGAAUCGGACUCUGAAAUACCUAAGAAUGACUGGAAACAAAAUUGAAAAUAAAGGUGGAAUGUUUUUUGCUGCAAUGCUGCAAAUUAAUUCAUCAUUAGAGAAAUUAGAUCUGGGUGACUGUGAUCUGGGAAUGCAAAGUGUGAUAGCAUUUGCUACAGUACUAACUCAAAACCAAGCAAUUAAGGCAAUAAACCUAAACCGACCUAUACUGUACAGUGAACAGGAAGAGUCUACAGUCCAUGUAGGCCGCAUGUUGAAAGAAAAUCACUGUCUUGUUGCACUACACAUGUGUAAGCAUGAUAUAAAAAACAGUGGUAUACAACAGUUAUGUGAUGCACUGUAUCUGAACAGUAGCCUGCGCUACCUUGAUGUCAGCUGCAACAAAAUAACUCAUGAUGGAAUGGUGUAUUUGGCUGAUGUACUGAAAAGCAACACUACCCUGGAAGUAAUAGAUCUUUCCUUUAACAGAAUAGAAAAUGCAGGCGCAAACUAUCUCAGUGAAACUCUUACUUCACACAACAGGAGUCUUAAAGCGUUAGUAUGGUUUUAUAUUUAAUCAAAAUAACAGAAAAGCAAAUUUUUAAAUACUAACCUCAAUCCCCUUAACUCUUAAGAUUAUAAUGAAAUAUGAAAACUCAGCUUCUAAACUGACAUAGUAUUAAGUUACAGUAAACAUUUACAUUUCUAUUUUUCAAAUGUAAUGUCUUUUACAAUUAGACUGAUUCUAUUAACGAUUCCUUCAAAUUAAUGAGAAAAUUUGCAUUGCUUAUAUUACUUAUCCUGAAUUCUAAUAGAAAACUCAGAAGCAUUCAAUAUGAUCAAGACUUUUAAAAGUAAGAAUGAACUAAAGAAUAAAAUACUUGGAUGCAUUUAUCCAGAAAAAUAUAUCUGCUAUCCACCCAAACAUUUACUGAAUAAUAUAAAACAGAAGACUUUCAAAAUGUAGUUAGCUCUACUAAGUACCUUAAGGAUCUAAUUAGAAAACUAAGUUUCUUGGAUUUUAGGAAUUAAAUGGUCAGUAUUUUUACCACUACAUUACAACAUACUGAAGAAUAAUGCUAAGACUACACAAGAAAGUGUUUGUAAUAAAUGUUGCUAAUUUUUGUAUUCUUUCCUUGUGGAAUUAUUGGUUUCAGGUUGUCAGUAGUCAGCAACAACAUAGAGGGAGAAGGACUUGUUGCACUUUCACAAUCAAUGAAAACAAAUCUCACUUUCUCUCAUAUCUACAUUUGGGGAAACAAAUUUGAUGAGGCUACGUGUAUAGUAAGUUUUAAGUUUUUUCCUUCACUGAAGGCUUUUUCUGGGAUCAUCUCUGUAACAUCAGAUAUUAUUUACAGGUGCCUCAGAAAUGGUUACACAGUGAGACACUGCAGUUUUGAUAAUUAACAUAAGUCUUAAAAUUAACUACUAGAGAGUUUGGUGGUUCAAAUAACCAAAGAUAUUAAAACUAUGUAUUAGUAUUACACAUCACUGAAUGACACAGUUCUAAUUCCUCUAAGGUUAAGAAAAAUCAUAAUUAUUGAUCAGAUGUAGCAAAAUUUCUGAUCUGCUCCCUAAUAAUUAUACCAAAAUAUGGAAUGGGAGAGAUAGAGUACAAGCUAUCAAAAUAUUUGGCAUGUUGCUCACAUAAAUACAGACAGCCUUUGAUACUACUUUCAAAACAGAAAUAAUGGUAACAGUUUUCAUUUGGAAAGAACGAGGGGGAAAAAGUAGAUGUUAAAAUUCUCAAAAUUUGCAAAAGGACUAACAAAAAUUCCACCACUAAAAAGAGUAAUAAAACAUAGAGUGUUGUCUAAACCACCCUCCCAAAAAAACCAACCCUUACUUUUAGAAAAACAUCCAUAAUUCUUUAGGUUCUACACAUCAGUAGCUGAAUAAGUUGAGUCUGGAACUGGAACUAAUGAUGAAUGACAAGCUAAAGCAAAAACCAACUUGACUUUUAAAUCUUUUAAUGUCUAAAUUUCCAUCUUUCUCCAUAUUGCCAACCUUACUGACAAACCAGUUCAACGUAUUUGUAUGACUCUGUUACAUAGAUACUAAGGAUCGUGGCUCAUGCCUGUAAUCCCAGCACUUUGGGAGGCUAAGGCGGGGGGAUCACGAGGUCAAGAGAUUGAGACCAUCCUGGCCAACAUGGUGAAACCCCAUCUCUACUAAAAGUACAAAAAUUAGCUGGGUGUGGUGGUGCGCUGGGCCUGUAGUCCCAGCUAUUCGGGAGGCUGAGGCAGGAGAAUCUCUUGAACCCAGGAGGCAGGGGUUGCAGUGAGCCGAGAUCGUGCCACUGCACUCCAGCUUGGCGACAGAGCAAGACUCUGUCUCAAAAAAAAAAAAAAAGUAUAAAAAUUCUACAAUGAAGAAAUAAUUAAUAGGUCCGCAUCCAAUACUAUGGAAUUGUCUGUUUUAGCCUAAAUCUGUAGAUUAGAUUCAGGGGGGUCAUGAACUCUAUAUAAUUGUAUGUCCAAAUCUGGGAUUCCCUUAAUUUUUCUGAGGAAUGGGUAACUAGCUAUCAGCAGAUUUUUGAGAAUGUAUACAAUAGGCCUCCUACCGAGCCCCCCUACCUAUUCCAAUUUAUGAACAUCUGUGGGACUUGAAAAUUUUGACCAUAGGAGCUUUGGUCCACAAAAUUGGUAGUAUAGAAAAUCAACUCUAGGAGUCACAAAAUGACAAAACAUGUCUAAUACAUUAAAAGUUAGAAAUAAGUUUUGCAAUAUUAUAAUUUCAUUCUGUGUAAUUAAAUGAAUAAAAAUCUAUUUACAAUACCUGGAAAAUAUUAAAAUUCAGCAAUGUUAUUCAGAAUAUUUUAUUUUAAACUACAAAUUAGCACAGCUAAUUUGAAUAUUUAAAUUUCCGUAAGCACUGUAAAUUGAAUACAUUUUUUCUUAAUGAUAUAGUUUUUUUCCUAAAAAUCCUAGGCAUAUUCAGACUUAAUUCAAAUGGGUUGUCUAAAACCAGACAAUACAGAUGUGGAGCCAUUUGUGGUAGAUGGACGUGUAUAUCUUGCAGAAGUCUCCAAUGGCCUUAAAAAGCAUUAUUAUUGGACAUCAACUUAUGGAGAAUCUUAUGACCACUCAUCUAAUGCAGGUUUUGCUCUUGUUCCAGUAGGUCAACAGCCAUGAAAAAGUAGCUGUAAAAUAAUUUUCAUACACUUGUCUUAUUGUUUCACAGAGAUUAAUAUUCUAUAGCCUAUUUUCUUUUAUAAAUUAAAACAAGUUACUUUUUUCAAAUGUGUAAAAGAUAAUGACUGUAUUAAACUUUGUAUAACUGUCUAUUGUGAAAAACUGAGUAGGGUAAUUUUUUAAAAGAAAUUUUACAAUAUAGAGACUAAAAUUCUAACCCUGGAGAAAGAGACCAAGGAACUAGACUAAAUUUCUUUUUAUAAUGAAAAUAUAACCAAGUAGUGAAAUAGCGUACAAGUAAAGGUCAUUGUAGGUAUCUAACUGAAAGUUAUUAAGUAGUAUUAAUAAAAAGGUUUGUGGUAGAAAAUUACCAGUGACUUUCAAAGGGUUUCAAAGUUCAGAAGUUGAAAAAGUAUUCUACCUAUCCUAUUUACGUGUUACAGACAGGUGUUACUAACAAUUUCAUAAAUACAGGCAAAUAUAUAUAAACAUAUACAUACCCCUUUCCCAACAAGCCAGUGCUGCCAGCUCUCCCACUCUCCUCUCAUAACCACUAUCCUGACUUCUAACCCCACAGAGUAGUUUUGCCUGUUCUUGACCUUUAUAUAAAUGGAAGCAUACAGUAUACACUC